CUUUCUGCAGCAGGAACCGCGGCUGCUGGACAAGAGGGGUGCGGUGGAUACUGACCUUUGCUCCGGCCUCGUGUAGCGUGAAGACACAGCGCAUCUCCCCGCUGUAGGCUUCCUCCCACAGAACCCGUUUCGGGCCUCAGAGCGUCUGGUGAGAUGCUGUUGCCGCUGCUGCUGCUGCUACCCAUGUGCUGGGCCGUGGAGGUCAAGAGGCCCCGGGGCGUCUCCCUCACCAAUCAUCACUUCUACGAUGAGUCCAAGCCUUUCACCUGCCUGGACGGUUCGGCCACCAUCCCAUUUGAUCAGGUCAACGAUGACUAUUGCGACUGCAAAGAUGGCUCUGACGAGCCAGGCACGGCUGCCUGUCCUAAUGGCAGCUUCCACUGCACCAACACUGGCUAUAAGCCCCUGUAUAUCCCCUCCAACCGGGUCAACGAUGGUGUUUGUGACUGCUGCGAUGGAACAGACGAGUACAACAGCGGCGUCAUCUGUGAGAACACCUGCAAAGAGAAGGGCCGUAAGGAGAGAGAGUCCCUGCAGCAGAUGGCCGAGGUCACCCGCGAAGGGUUCCGUCUGAAGAAGAUCCUUAUUGAGGACUGGAAGAAGGCACGGGAGGAGAAGCAGAAAAAGCUCAUUGAGCUACAGGCUGGGAAGAAGUCUCUGGAAGACCAGGUGGAGAUGCUGCGGACAGUGAAGGAGGAAGCUGAGAAGCCAGAGAGAGAGGCCAAAGAGCAGCACCAGAAGCUGUGGGAAGAGCAGCUGGCUGCUGCCAAGGCCCAACAGGAGCAGGAGCUGGCGGCUGAUGCCUUCAAGGAGCUGGAUGAUGACAUGGACGGGACGGUCUCGGUGACUGAGCUGCAGACUCACCCGGAGCUGGACACAGAUGGGGAUGGGGCGUUGUCAGAAGCGGAAGCUCAGGCCCUCCUCAGUGGGGACACACAGACAGACGCCACCUCUUUCUACGACCGCGUCUGGGCCGCCAUCAGGGACAAGUACCGGUCCGAGGCACUGCCCACCGACCUUCCAGCACCUUCUGCCCCUGACUUGACGGAGCCCAAGGAGGAGCAGCCGCCAGUGCCCUCGUCGCCCACAGAGGAGGAGGAGGAGGAGGAGGAGGAGGAGGAAGAAGAGGCUGAAGAAGAGGAGGAGGAGGAGGAUUCCGAGGUGCAGGGGGAGCAGCCCAAGGAGGCCCCACCGCCACUGUCACCCCCGCAGCCGGCCAGCCCUGCUGAGGAAGACAAAAUGCCGCCCUACGACGAGCAGACGCAGGCCUUCAUCGAUGCUGCCCAGGAGGCCCGCAACAAGUUCGAGGAGGCCGAGCGGUCGCUGAAGGACAUGGAGGAGUCCAUCAGGAACCUGGAGCAAGAGAUUUCUUUUGACUUUGGCCCCAACGGGGAGUUUGCUUACCUGUACAGCCAGUGCUACGAGCUCACCACCAACGAAUACGUCUACCGCCUCUGCCCCUUCAAGCUUGUCUCGCAGAAACCCAAACUCGGGGGCUCUCCCACCAGCCUUGGCACCUGGGGCUCAUGGAUUGGCCCCGACCACGACAAGUUCAGUGCCAUGAAGUAUGAGCAAGGCACGGGCUGCUGGCAGGGCCCCAACCGCUCCACCACCGUGCGCCUCCUGUGCGGGAAAGAGACCAUGGUGACCAGCACCACAGAGCCCAGUCGCUGCGAGUACCUCAUGGAGCUGAUGACGCCAGCCGCCUGCCCGGAGCCACCGCCUGAAGCACCCACCGAAGACGACCAUGACGAGCUCUAGCUGGAUGGGCGCAGAGAACCUCAAGAAGGCAUGAAGCCAGCCCCUGCAGUGCCGUCCACCCGCCCCUCUGGGCCUGCCUGUGGCUCUGUUGCCCUCCUCUGUGGCGGCAGGACCUUUGUGGGGCUUCGUGCCCUGCUCUGGGGCCCAGGCGGGGCUGGUCCACAUUCCCAGGCCCCAACAGCCUUCAAAGAUGGGUAAAGGAGCUUGCCCUCCCUGGGCCCCCCACCUUGGUGACUCGCCCCACCACCCCCAGCCCUGUCCCUGCCACCCCUCCUAGUGGGGACUAGUGAAUGACUUGACCUGUGACCUCAAUACAAUAAAUGUGAUCCCCCACCCAAA